GUCCGGACCGGAGGGGCAGUGGGCGCCAUCUUCUUCUGGGCUCACUGAGGGUCUACCUGUUUUGGGGAGGCUGCUGCGACGAAGAGUUCCCUCAGCCUCCGGCCUUGUGUGUCCGACUCGGCAGCAGUGGUGUGUGUUUAUUGCCAAGUGCGAAGCAGUUCCCCUCGGGGCGCCGGGGGUGGGGAGGGCUGGGCGACCAAGCCGGAAGAACGGGGAAAGGCGGGACCGGCGGCCGCGCCAGUAUCUAGCGUAGCUCCUGCCGUUAGGGCACCCUCUUUUCUUGCUAAAACACCGACUCUUCCUUUCCCGUCAGCUUCCAUGUGGUGGUGUAUGUGCGCUUCCCAGGGAUCUUGAGAGUGAAGAUCUCGAAGGAUUUCAUAGGUAUAUUUUUUUCUUUGCUAUGUCAUCGUAGUCAGUGGUGGCAGAAAAGCGCUGCAGGCCCAGCUCGUUAGGCUUGAGAAGGGCAAGUGUUUUCAGUUAGAUCUGGGGGCAGUUCACCCUCUGGCGAGUUAGGGUGGAAUGUUUGCCCUUGAGACGGCGUAACGGAAAGGCACGGAGGUUGGGCGGUCCAGGUUAAUUUGAAGGCUGAUUUUGGCUGAAAGUCUGGCGACAACAUCGGAUCCCACGUAGCAACUUUGGCCUGGCGCGAAAGAAGGAAGCUCUGACCCCUGGGAGUUGUGGACAAAGGCUUUGGGCUGUAGAAUCGAUGCCUUCGGAUGAUUCCCGUUUGAGGAUGUUGGGAGAAAUCCUGUGCCAUGUGGAUUCGUCUUCAUUUACAGUUCUUCCUAGGGACUGUGGCUCUCAUUGGUCAUUCCUUUGGUUUUUAUUUUAAACAUCUACAUUAUAAAAGGUGGAUCAUCGUAAAGAAUAAUUAUGGGUUGGUGUAGAUUAUUUUCUGCAGGGGAAACUCACGUUUAGAGUGUGAAUAUGCUACAUCAUGACCUUGGGCUUUACGAAGUAGUCGCAGAGUUAAAAAAAAUUCUCUCCCUCACCAUAUCUGGAAAAUGACUUUUUCUUCGCUAGUUAAAAAUCAAAUGGAUCUGAUGAGAUAUUACUUAUUUAAAUUCUGUCUCCCUCCCGUUUCCCUCUCUGUAUCCCCUUAAGUCUUGAUUAGAAGAGGCACGUUACGUAUUGUUUAGUUAUAAUGGUGAUUAAGUGGGAUGAAUCGUUGGAUAAAAAUAGCAGUUAUUUAAAAUGCGCUUUAAAUUUCACUGACUUAAGUGAUCUUUUAGGGACCCACUCUUCUUUUCAUAGAAAUUUUAACAGAUUAUUGUCUUCAAAUGAACACAAAGGCACAAAAAUACUUUUUGCAUUCAUAACUAGAAAAACGCAAAAUUUUAAUUGCAGACUACUUGAGGGUAAUUUUCGUGUUUUGCUUUUGUGUAAUUUAGUGUGUUAAGAGUUGAAUUUCUGGAGAAUUUGCUUAAGGAAAUAUAGCAUGUUGGAACCACAGAAGUGCCCAUUUUGAGAGCUGGUCUCUUACAGUUGGUCUCCAAGGUGUGUUAUUGUAGAGGCAUAAAUGGUACAUUACCCUACUGUCUCAAGGGUAGAGAAGUUUAAGCAUUAGUUUUGUUUAACUGUGGCAAAUGAGAAUAAACUUUCUAAAUAGUCUGCUUGAAUUGGAAUUCAUGAGAUUUGUGCUCAUGAAACUACUUGGUUAAAAGAUAGUUUUUAAGUGAGGUAGGAUAAAUUACUAGAGUUUUUUUGAAUUUGAGAUAUAAUUAUUCCUUGAAACGUCUCUAAUUUCUCUUGUAGAUGAAUUUAUGUUCCCAGGGUAAAUCCCGUUAAAAUUUUUUUAAAAGCUUAGGAGAGACAAGAAUAUGUAUAGCUUAUGGUGCUUUCUAAAAUAUCUUAAAAAGAGUAGCUAAGCCAAUUUGCAUAGGAGGGAGUCUUGGGACUUUAAUAUGGAUAAAGUAAGUAUUCCAGAAGCCAUUUGUAGUUUUUGUUGAAGUGUUAGUAUGGAUAUUGGUUUGUUGAAGAAAAUAGGCUUUUUUUCUUUUUUUGUUACUGUGCAAAUACUUUAAUAGCAAACCUGAUUAAUAUUUUUCAGAUGUAGAAUGUGUGAAGUAAUUUGAUGUCUUUGCUAGUUUAGCUUCUGGUUAAUCUACGUACCCUUUUUUAAAGGAAAACAGACCUCAGUGAAUGUAUCUUCAGACCCCCACUUUGGGGAACAGUGGUACUUAAGUGUAAGUACUGGAUUCUGGAUUAACGCAACAUUUAUUUGUACAUUAAAGACAUGUAAAUUACUCCAGGCGCAGUGGCUCAUACCUGUAAAUCCUAGCACUGUGGGAGGCUGAGGUGAGCUGAUUGCUUGAGCCCAUGAGUUCCCUACCAGCCUGGGCAACAUGGUGAAACCCUGGCUCUACAAAAAAUACAAAAAUUAGCCGGGUGUGGUGGUGCACACCUGUAGUCCCAGCUACUGGGGAGGCUGAGGUGGGAGCAUUGCCUGAGCCUGGGUAAGUCGAGGCUGUAGUGAGCCAAGAUCGCACCAGUGCACUCCAGCCUGGGUAGCAGAGCAAGAGAGACCCUGUCUCCCCCACCAAAGAAAGUGAGUGUAAAUUAUAAUUAUUUAUUUGGCAAGUCUUCAUGAAAUAGUUUGGGUAUCCCUGAAAGUAUUAAACGCAAACUUCUUUAAAAAAUUACAUUGAGAUUUUUCAGUAAACGGGUAAUCCCAGUAUUCCAAGUUAAUUUUUAAUUUUACUUUUCUACAUCAUCAUUUGGGUUUCCUUAGUAGAGUGCAGAAUAGUUGUUUGAAAUGGAAAUCUGCUAUUGGCAUUAUUAAUAAGAUAAAUAGCAUUUUCUGUUUGGCUUGAGAUGAAUUGUAACAGUUACUAUUUUUGCAAUAGGAGUGGUAUUGAGAUUUUUAACUUUAGGGAUAUUGUAGUAUUUGCCUUAAUUAUACUGGCUUCAUGAAAUUUGGUUCUGUGCUUGGAUGUAUGAGCUGUUUAUAUAGACCUUUAAAUUGUAUCCAAACAAUAGCCCAUAGGUUUGGAUUUAUUGUUUUAAAAAUUGAUUUUUGAAUUUCAGGCUUUGCUGUUUUAUUCAUUUAUUGUGUAAUUUUGAAUGGUUGCCUUAAUUUGAUUUGGUCUUAUGUUUUGAAAGGGAGGAGAACAGCACGAGAGUUGGAUAUAAAUAUGUACUAGAUUUUUGGAUUUUCAUGUGGCAAAAUGAUUGAAGUUCUUUUUUUUUUUUUUUUUUUUUUGAACUUUGGGUAUUGAGAUUUUACUUGUAGAACAGUUUUUUGAAGUAGAUGUAAAACUUGUGUACAGCAAAAUGUAUAGACCCUAAGGAUAGAAUUCAGUAAACCUUGAUAAAUUUAUACACCCAUGUAACUACUGCUGCAUUCAAAAUAUGUAACAUUUCCAUCACUCCUUUCUUCGUGCUACUUCCAAUCAAGAGCAGUUGUUAAAUUUUCGGCAAGUUUCAAAUUUUUAAAUAAUUUUUAUAUGUCUAUUUGGAUAUUGUAUCUCCUUUUUGCAGAAGGAUGAUUAAUUUCCCCUUGGAACAAAAGACCAUUUUGUAACACCCGUAAUUGUGGUUCCUUAUUCUGCUUCACUUUUGAUAGUUAAGUUGCUUUUACAGAGUUAACAGGUCUCCAAGAAAUUUUAAAAAAGGUCAUUAUUGCUGUGGUUUGAGCUCAGCAUGGCUGUAGUCAUCCGUUUACUGGGGCUUCCUUUUAUUGCGGGGCCUGUGGAUAUUCGUCACUUCUUCACGGGAUUGACUAUUCCUGAUGGAGGAGUGCAUAUAAUUGGAGGGGAAAUUGGGGAGGCUUUUAUUAUUUUUGCAACAGAUGAAGAUGCAAGACGUGCCAUAAGUCGUUCAGGAGGGUUUAUCAAGGAUUCAUCUGUAGAGCUCUUUCUUAGUAGCAAGGCAGAAAUGCAGAAGACUAUAGAAAUGAAAAGAACUGAUCGUGUAGGAAGAGGGCGUCCAGGAUCUGGGACAUCAGGGGUUGACAGCCUGUCUAAUUUUAUUGAGUCUGUUAAGGAAGAAGCAAGUAAUUCUGGAUAUGGCUCUUCAAUUAAUCAAGAUGCUGGGUUUCAUACUAAUGGUACAGGACAUGGUAAUUUAAGGCCAAGAAAGACAAGGCCAUUGAAGGCCGAGAAUCCUUACUUGUUUCUACGAGGUUUGCCUUACCUAGUAAAUGAAGAUGAUGUACGUGUCUUUUUCUCUGGUUUGUGCGUGGAUGGAGUAAUUUUCUUAAAACAUCAUGAUGGCCGAAAUAAUGGUGAUGCCAUAGUAAAAUUUGCUUCAUGUGUUGAUGCUUCAGGAGGUCUUAAAUGUCAUAGAAGUUUUAUGGGUUCAAGAUUUAUAGAAGUAAUGCAAGGAUCAGAACAACAGUGGAUUGAGUUUGGUGGUAAUGCAGUUAAGGAGGGUGACGUUCUUAGGAGAUCUGAAGAACAUUCUCCACCAAGAGGAAUUAAUGAUAGACAUUUUCGAAAACGGUCUCAUUCAAAAUCUCCCAGAAGAACACGUUCUCGUUCCCCUCUUGGAUUUUAUGUUCACUUAAAAAAUCUGUCCCUCAGUAUUGACGAAAGAGAUUUAAGAAAUUUCUUUAGAGGUACUGAUCUGACUGAUGAACAGAUUAGGUUUUUAUAUAAAGAUGAAAAUAGAACAAGAUAUGCCUUUGUGAUGUUCAAGACUCUGAAAGACUAUAAUACCGCUCUGAGUUUACAUAAGACUGUUUUACAAUAUCGUCCAGUUCAUAUUGAUCCAAUUUCUAGAAAACAAAUGCUGAAGUUCAUUGCACGUUAUGAAAAGAAGAGAUCAGGGUCACUAGAGAGAGAUAGGCCCGGACAUGUUUCACAAAAAUACUCUCAAGAAGGUAACUCUGGCCAGAAACUGUGCAUCUAUAUAAGAAAUUUUCCAUUUGAUGUUACAAAAGUUGAAGUGCAGAAGUUCUUUGCAGACUUUCUUCUUGCUGAGGAUGACAUUUACUUGCUUUAUGAUGACAAAGGUGUUGGUCUGGGAGAAGCAUUAGUGAAAUUUAAAUCAGAAGAACAGGCCAUGAAAGCUGAACGUUUAAACCGACGAAGAUUCCUAGGGACAGAGGUGUUAUUAAGACUUAUAUCUGAGGCACAAAUACAGGAGUUUGGUGUAAAUUUUUCUGUGAUGUCCAGUGAAAAAAUGCAAGCUCGCUCACAGUCACGUGAGCGAGGUGACCAUUCCCAUUUAUUUGACUCAAAAGACCCACCAAUAUACUCAGUUGGUGCUUUUGAAAACUUUAGACAUCAGCUAGAGGACUUGAGGCAACUGGAUAACUUCAAGCAUCCCCAGAGGGAUUUCCGGCAGCCUGACAGGCACCCUCCAGAAGACUUCCGACACUCCUCAGAGGACUUUAGGUUCCCCCCGGAGGACUUCAGGCACUCCCCAGAGGACUUCAGGCGACCUAGGGAGGAAGACUUCAGGCGGCCUUCUGAGGAGGACUUCAGGCGCCCUUGGGAGGAAGAUUUCAGGCGCCCUCCGGAGGAUGACUUCAGGCACCCUAGGGAGGAGGACUGGAGGAGGCCCCUUGAGGAGGACUGGAGGCGGCCACUGGAGGAGGAUUUCAGGCGGUCUCCCACGGAGGACUUCAGGCAGCUCCCCGAGGAGGACUUCAGGCAACCCCCUGAGGAGGACUUAAGGUGGCUCCCAGAGGAAGAUUUCAGGCGGCCACCUGAGGAGGACUGGAGACGGCCCCCAGAGGAGGACUUUAGGCGGCCUCUUCAGGGAGAAUGGAGGCGACCACCCGAGGAUGACUUCAGGCGGCCCCCAGAGGAGGAUUUCAGGCAUUCCCCUGAGGAGGACUUCAGGCAGUCACCCCAGGAGCAUUUCCGGAGGCCACCUCAGGAGCAUUUCCGUCGGCCACCCCCAGAGCAUUUCCGGAGACCACCUCCAGAGCAUUUUAGGCGGCCUCCCCCAGAGCACUUCCGGCGGCCACCCCCAGAGCACUUCAGGCGGCCACCCCCAGAGCAUUUCAGGCGCCCGCCCCCGGAGCACUUCCGGAGACCGCCCCAGGAGCAUUUCAGGCGGCCGCCUCAGGAGCAUUUCAGGCGCUCCCGAGAGGAAGAUUUCAGGCACCCACCAGAUGAAGACUUCAGGGGCCCUCCUGAUGAAGACUUUAGGCACCCUCCUGAUGAGGACUUCAGGAGCCCCCAGGAGGAAGAUUUUAGAUGCCCUUCUGAUGAGGACUUCAGGCAGCUCCCAGAGGAAGACCUUAGGGAAGCUCCGGAGGAGGACCCUAGACUUCCUGACAAUUUUAGACCUCCUGGUGAGGAUUUUAGGAGCCCGCCUGAUGAUUUUAGAAGUCACCGCCCUUUUGUGAAUUUUGGUCGCCCAGAAGGUGGCAAGUUUGAUUUUGGAAAGCAUAAUAUGGGAAGUUUUCCUGAGGGGAGAUUUAUGCCUGAUCCAAAAAUAAAUUGUGGUUCAGGUAGAGUAACUCCUAUUAAGAUAAUGAAUCUUCCAUUUAAAGCUAAUGUGAAUGAAAUUUUAGACUUUUUCCAUGGUUACAGAAUCAUACCUGAUUCAGUUUCGAUACAGUAUAAUGAGCAAGGCUUACCUACAGGGGAAGCCAUUGUUGCUAUGAUAAACUAUAAUGAAGCUAUGGCUGCUAUUAAAGAUCUAAAUGAUAGGCCAGUUGGGCCCCGAAAAGUUAAGUUAACUUUGCUGUAGAGAGAGAGCAUUUCUAAAUUCAGUUAUCUUCCUUGCAGUAUUGAUGGAGUAAAAUACAUUUGUUUUAAAAAAGUGUUUUUUUUUUAAAUUAUCUAAUGAAAUAUUUUAUUUUUGACCUGUGAAUAGAACAAAUGUAAAUAGUAGAAUGUGAAUCUGGUUUUCUUUUGCUUGCAAAUUGCCAUUCUUUUUUUUUUUCAAAUUUAAAAUUACACAUGCUGUUUUUUUCUUUGAUGGGGAGAAAGAACUCAUUCCCUGAGUUCAUUCAUUUUUGUUGAUGUCAUCGGUAAUCUUCAAGACUUAUUGAAGUAGAGUUGUAUUUGGGGAAGAUACAUUUUAUAUUCACUUUUUUUUUUCUUUCUGUAGUCUACCUCUUUUACUCAAACUGUAUAAGGAAAUAGUGACUGAUUGUUCAGGUUUGGCAUUUUCAUUGCUACCUGCCUGCAGAAUUAAUGCCCUCUUCCUUGUCUAAGAUAUUACUGUGUUAAGUGUCCUGUUAAUUAUAAAUAGUUCAAAAUGGACAGACUGUCAACUUGAAAUUUACUUAUGUAAAAAGCUUAGGUGAUUCUUAGGGUUUCCAUGUUCAUAACUUUACAAAGCUUUAUAAAAAUAAAAUUGCAACUUAAUAGAGCUAAUUAACUUGUAUUUGUAUAAAAAGAAAAAAGAAUUGCAGCUCGAUAUUGUGAAGUUUUUCAAUAACUUCAUUAAACCAUAUUUAUGAUGGGAGGGACCAGACAUUCUAUAGUAAUAAUGUAUAGUGCUGUGUAUAAUUCCAUGGUUUCUUCAACAUCUUAUCAACCAAGUAAAAUUAAUACAAGAUACGCAAAAGAUAGUAAAAUAAGAAUCUAAUUAUAGGUGCAAGGGGACUCAGGCUUAUGCUGGAAGAAUCUGACAAGUGGUAUAGUUUGUUUUUCUAGGAAGAAUUUACUGAUGAGUCACAUAACUUGCAUGUAAUAUUAGGUUCUCAUUUUUUAGCUUCGAAACUGUGUCCAUGCAAAGACUCUAUAACUGUUAAGACUUGUGUGGUUGAAUUUUGACUUCUUUGAUAUUCAGCAUUUAGUGCAUACAUUUUGCAACUAGGGAAUUUGAUUUUCUAUACCCACAAUAAUAUUUAUGGCUAACAUUUAUUAGGCACUUACUAUGUGCUAGGCACUGUAAGCACUUUACAUGCAUAAUCUCGGUAUUCCCUGUGAGUACAGGGUUAAUUAUUUACCUCUAUUUCACAAAUGAGAUAAUGAAGUGGGAUGAAGUGCGAGGUUAAGCAACUUGCUUGAAGUCAUAGGUAGUAAAUCGUGGGGCCAAUUUUAACCCAGACAGACCACUGACUCCAGUUCAUGCUUUUGCUGCCUCACUUUUUUAAGUGGUAUUUUUAAUUAGGAAGACCAUGCUAAAGAUACUUUCAAGGAUAAAUGAUUAUUUUCUCACUUCAAUUGUUGGUUUAAAAUUAGCAUAAAUAGGUAAAACCAGCAUGCUCAAACACUGAGCUCAAACAUUAACAUUACUAAUAAAAAAAAAAAGAGUGACUUUAAAAGUUUCUUUCUAUCCAGGGUUUCUCUUGGGAUACUCAUAUGGUAUAUUACUGGCUUAUAUUUCAAAAUUAUUUUAUUCAACAUGAUUGACUUUGGCCUUUUAUAAUUUACAUAAAACAUAAUUUUCCUCAGUUCUGUAAUCCAGAUUUUCCCCAUUGAGUAAAUAAUACAAUUAAAUUUACAUAUGGUAAUUUAGACAUUUAAUAGGAUAUUGCAUAGGUAGAAUACUUUGUCAGUACUUAGUUACUACCUAUAUGUAUUUUUGUGUUACUUUUCAGUGAUUUAAAGAAAUCUAACAGAAAUCUGCUUAAAUUUGUUUUAAAUAGUGAAUAUCCUGCUUGCUAUGGAAUGAAUAAACAGGUAAAUUUGAUAUGAAAAAGCACCUCAGUAUGAUUCUUUAAAGUAUAAGCUUGUAAGUAGCUAGGAUAAUGUUAAAUUGAUUGUUUGGAAUAUCCAAACCAAGCACAAUGAAGAAAGUAGAAAUGAUAUUUUUAAUUGAGCAAAGAUUGUAUAGAUGGUUCAUUUGGUCACCCAUUUUGAAUAAUAUAUGGAAAGUUAAAAAAUGCUUCUCAGAUACAAAGGAAUAAAGCUAAGAUGAAGCUUAACGUGAGGGAUUACUUACUGUGGAAUUGCAUUUCAAACUGGGCUGAGGUGGGAUGGUGGUGGUAGAUAAGAGGCCAGCUAGAGUAAACAUAAGCUUUGUAGUUUUAUUAUUUUAAGAGUCAGAGUCUUGUUCUGCUGGCCAGGCUGGAGUGCAGUGGUCUGAUAAUGGUUCACUGCAGCUUCUAACUCCUGGGCUCAAGCUGUCUUCCUGCCUCAGCCUCCUGAGAGCUGGGACUACAGGUGUGUGCCACCUUGUCUGGCUAAAUUUUUUAUUAUUUGUAGAGACAGAGUCUCACUGUGUUGCCCAGGCUGUUCUCAAAUUUCUGGCCUCAAGCAAUCCUCACUCCUUGGUCUCCCAGAAUGUGUUGGGAUUACAGGUGUGAGCCACUGUGCCCAGCCUUGUAUUUUGAUUUUUAAAUUAAUUUAUAUGAAUAUUUCCUUUUACCCUAUAAUGUAUCAGGGCUUAAUAUUUUUAAACUUCAUUAUAAAAAGUUGAUUACAGAAAGUGGUAUCUUCUAGUUGGGAGCCAUCUUUGCACAUCUCUCUCCAACUCUGCCUUUAGUGAUAUGUCAAUAACAAAUUGGCCAUGGCAGGAGUAUUUUACACCAUGGAAAGUGAUAAAUGCAGCAAAUCAAGGAAUUCCCCUCCUGUUGUCCCCUCAGAAAGCCAGCUUCCCAGCACCUCAUCAAUUUCAAAUAUAAAAAAAGAAUAGUAAAUUUUCAUGUACACAUCACUCAGCUUCAGUAAUUGUCGUCUCAUAGCCAGUUUUUCCUCUCCUAUCCUCAAGGUAUACCAGGUACACUGGAGGUGUAUUCUCUAGCCUGAUACCCAGUGGCAUUUGUCUUAAAGCCAAACAUUUUUGUCUAGAAAUUAUCUAAAAAAAUGUAGAUCAUGUCUAGAAAGUCAAUCCCACAACCAAGAGAUAGGUAAAAAUCAUGUUAGGAGUGCAUUUCUAUUAAUUUACUGAGAUCACUGUUAAGAGCAGUGAUUCUUGAUCCAUAUAUCACCUGUUAAGUAGUGACCUUGCUGCCUCUGUUUUUGCAGUAAAUAUUAGCUGUUGUUUAUUGAGCUGUAUUAGAUACUAUAUGAUGUAUAAUUAUGUAUGAAUUAACUAUCAUUUAAUUCUGAUAAUCCUAGUAAAUGUACUACAGGUUGAGUAUUCCUAAUCUGGUAAUCUGAAAUUUCACAUGCUCCGAAAAUCACAAACUUUUUGAGUGCCAACAUGAUGCUCAAAGAAAAUGCUCAUUGCAGCAUUUAAGAUUUCAGAUUUUUGGGUUAGGAAUGUUGAACUGGUAUAAUGCAAAUACUCCAAAAUCUGAAGAAAUCCAAAGUCUUAAAUACUUCUGGUCCCAAGCACUUCAGAUAAAGGAUACUCAAUUUGUAUUCCUAUUUUGGAGAUAAGAGAUGGAGACUUACAGGCUGGGUUGGUUGGAUUGGUUGCCUGUUUUUUGUUGUUGUUGUAGUGGAAGCUAGGAAUGGUUUUUCACAUUUUUUAAGUGUACUUAAGUCUUACAUGGUUACAUAGUUACCUGUAUAAUAGUCUUGAAUUUGCCUAAACCCACGAAGAAUAACAGUAUUUGCUAUCUGGCCCUUUAAGAAGUUUGCCAACCUAGGCUGGUCUAAAUAAUGAAAAUUUUACAUUAAUGAAAGUAUUUUCAUGGAUAGUAUUCCUUUUGUUCUUAGAAUAUUUCUUUGAGGUAGGCAGAAUGUAUGUUUUAUUCCAGAAUUACUGUUUUACGCAGUUUUAACUUUACAAACAAGGCAAAUAAUGCUCAAGAGAAGUUGCUAUUUAGUAAGCAGCAAAAUAAUAACUCUGUUGUUUUCCCCCGAAGUACAACCAAAUUUAAAUACUGAGUGAGGAAGCAGUAAAUAUCCAAUGAUAUCUUGAGUUUCUUAAGAAUAUCAAUUUAGGGUUUUAAAAUGUUUUAAAUAUUUUACAAAAAAGUACUGAAACAACUUUGUCACUUAGGACUAUUCUCAGGAAGGAGUGCUUUGUUAAGAACAGAGCCAUGAUUGACAAAGUCAGAAGCUUUCUAGAAAGUCUUUAUUUUUCUGUUAUGAAUAAUUGCAUUUUCUAAUUAUCCCAAAUGAUUUUAUAAAUUCCGUAACUUUUAUAUGCCUGCCUGGGAUCCAUGAAAUAAAAGUAUUCCUUACCAAAAGAGAAGCAUCAGAUACACUGAAAGGCUCAAUGUUUUAUAUUUUCAGAAAUAAAAGUGACUGUAUACCCUUUUAUUAACUAUAUGGUAGCUUGGUAAAAUUUUUAUAGAAUUUUUAAUGAUCUAUGGUGUUCUAUGAUGAGGCAACAUUCCACCAAAUUAGCCUUCCAAAAGUUGCAGUAUCAUGUAUAAUUAUGACAGCAGUUUUGUUUUAAAACCAGAGUCAGAUUGAAUGUAGCUUUUUUACAGCUGAAAUUUAUGCCUUAUGUGUAUUCAUAAAACAUUGAUAACUUAGUGUCACAUUAUCUUUACUCUUUGGUUAUACUCUUCUUGAAAAGUAAAUUUACUUAUCAAAUGAUAAAGUUUCAGGGAAAGUUAAAAAAAGUUUUUUUUCUUAAGGCUUCAUGGAAUAGAAUUCCAUGAAUCAUAAUGACUACGUAAGACCCUUUUCUGGUAAUGAAAGCAUGGAGUCUUAACCAAAAAGCUAAGCAGAAUUGUUAGAUCUUUUGGUUUCUGUCAUAAUGUACUAUUGGAACUUCAAGUAGAUAUAGUACAUUAAUAUGAAAUACUUUGAAAUACACCAUCUUUAAAAAAAAAGGCACUUACACAAAAAUCAUGUAACACUAGGUAGGAUGUUGAAAUGACUGGUAUGCAAUAUUUUUUAAAGCCUUCAUUUUUGGUCAGCAUAAGUUUCCUUUAAUUAUUUUUCUGUUUCCAGUUGGACUUCACUUUGAGGCUUAACAUAGCAAAGUGAGUAUAAAGUUCUACAAUUUAGUCAUUGUGGAUUUCAAGUCAUUUAUGAUGAAAAUGGAAAUGUGUAGUUUACUUAAGAAAAUUUUCUUCUUCUGUAACAUCUAACUCGUCAUCCUCAUCAUCUUCUGCUUGUUGAUCCUUUCUUAGUCGACAAGUGGAUACCUGUUAAAAGUUAACACACUUUUUAAAAUAAAAAUACUAACUUAAAAAAA